AGAACAGCCCAAGAUGGCCGACUUCGAUGAUCGUGUGUCGGAUGAGGAGAAGGUACGCAUAGCUGCUAAAUUCAUCACUCAUGCACCCCCAGGGGAAUUUAAUGAAGUAUUCAAUGACGUUCGGCUACUACUUAAUAAUGACAAUCUCCUCAGGGAAGGGGCAGCACAUGCAUUUGCCCAGUAUAACAUGGAUCAGUUCACGCCUGUGAAGAUAGAAGGAUAUGAAGAUCAGGUCUUAAUUACAGAGCACGGUGACCUGGGUAAUAGCAGAUUUUUAGAUCCAAGAAACAAAAUUUCCUUUAAAUUUGACCACUUACGGAAAGAAGCAAGUGACCCCCAGCCAGAAGAAGCAGAUGGAGGUCUGAAGUCUUGGAGAGAAUCCUGUGACAGUGCUUUAAGAGCCUAUGUGAAAGACCAUUAUUCCAACGGCUUCUGUACUGUUUAUGCUAAAACUAUCGAUGGGCAACAGACUAUUAUUGCAUGUAUUGAAAGCCACCAGUUUCAGCCUAAAAACUUCUGGAAUGGUCGUUGGAGAUCAGAGUGGAAGUUCACCAUCACACCACCUACAGCCCAGGUGGUUGGCGUGCUUAAGAUUCAGGUUCACUAUUAUGAAGAUGGCAAUGUUCAGUUGGUUAGUCAUAAAGAUGUACAGGAUUCACUAACUGUUUCGAAUGAAGCCCAAACUGCCAAGGAGUUUAUUAAAAUCAUAGAGAAUGCAGAAAAUGAGUAUCAGGGGACUCAAGCAUAUCCAUUGACUAUAGCAUUACUUUUCUGUUCACAACCAGCCCCAUUUCUGUUCAAGCAACUCAUCUUCAAUUAUCUAUUGCAGACAGCAAUUAGUGAAAACUAUCAAACAAUGUCAGAUACCACAUUCAAGGCCUUGCGCCGGCAGCUUCCAGUUACCCGCACCAAAAUCGACUGGAACAAGAUACUCAGCUACAAGAUUGGCAAAGAAAUGCAGAAUGCUUAAAGGCUGAAUGUAGGAUUCUUCAGUAUGUGGAAAGACAAGGAUUCAACGUGUGGUCAUAUGAUAAAUAAGUGAUUUAUAAACAAGAGUGAUAUUUUGCUAGGGCUUUCAAAGUUAACCGGUUUUCUAGCCUCAUGGAAUACUGUUGAACCUAUAGCGUUGUCUUGAUUCUUUUGUGUUCUCUGCCUUGUAAUUUUCUGUUACUGCUAUAUCUACGUGUAAAUCUUUUUUUCUUUUUUUUUUUUUUUUUUUGGUUAAUUCUGCCACAUUUAAUGUUGGUGAGAGAGUGAUCUAUCCUAAUGACAUUUUACUGUUUAAAAAAGUUUCCUAGCCAUGAAGCCCUGCUACUGAUUUAGACAAGGUAUUAUGGUCAUUACUUUGUACCCCUAUCCUUCCAAGCACUUCUGGUACUUCAGUCGUUUUUACUGAUCCACCAACACCUAAAGAGGCUAUGCUACAGUCUCUAGCUAAAUGGAAGACACAUUCAUCCUUCUCCCUCUGACUGCUUUGAUCAUCAUUUAUUGCAUCUCAUAACUAAUUUUCUAAAGUUUGGAUUGGGACUUUUCAGGUCCUUUUUGGAGGGCAAAGGAAGUGCCAGCUUCUCUGGGGAACUUGUUUUUAAAUCCAAAGACUUGAACCACAUUCCCUGCACAUGAACAUGUUUGCUUUUAUCCCUUCUCUCAUUGUCUCCUUCCCAUCUUAGUACCAUUGUAGUUAUAAACAUCUGCAUUUUUUAGAAGCAUUUUACCCAUUUAUUUUUUUAAACAUUCAAGAACUGCUGACGUACUGUGGAUGUAGAGUAUAAAACUUGAAAAAUGCAGAUGUUGAAGGAAUAAUAGGUAUCUUGUGCUUUAAUACUUUAUGGCAGGAUUGUACUAUAAGCAAAUGAAUUAAACAGCUAUGUAAAUCAUAAAGAAAAACUAAAAAUGAACCAAAGUGAAAGGAUAACUUCCAGGCAGUAUCUUUCUAUUGUAACCUGUUAUUUAAGGAAAUACUAGUGAUUUCUUCUAAAUAGGAUGUAAAACUUCUUUCAAAUUACUCUUCCUCAGUCCUGCCUGCCAAGAACUCAAGUGUAACUGUGAUAAAAUAACCUUUCCCAGGUAUAUUGGCAGGUAUGUGUGUAAUCUCAGAAUACACAGGUGACAUAGAUAUGAUAUGACAACUGGUAAUGGUGGAUUCAUUUACAUUGUUUACACUUCUAUGACCAGGCCUUAAGGGAAGGUCAGUUUUUUAAAAAACCAAGUAGUGUCUUCCUACCUAUCUCCAGAUACAUGUCAAAAAAAGAAAGGUGUUUGUGCUUCCGUUUUGUUUCUGCUCAGUAAUAUAGUCAAGCAAGUUUGUUCCAGGUGACCCAUUGAGCUGUGUAUGCAUUUUUGUUUAUUUCAAUAAAAUAUAUUUGUAUUAUUUGUCCUUCAUACUAUCCAUCCAUACCACACUAUCUUCUGUAUCAGGUAGUCUAAUAGAAAUAUACCUGUUUUGUUCUAAAA